GUCAGUCCCCGCGCUUUUCGGAGGCUGCCAGCGUCCCACACCAGCCGCAGGUGAAAACCGGCAGAAAGACAUUAAGAGAUUUUCCUGCAGUCACUGCUGGCAGAUGAUAGAGCCAGGAUUUGAAAGCAGGCAGCCUGGCUCCAGACCCUGUGCUCUUAACUCCCGUUUUGCAUCAAGAACAGAAUCCUAUGAAAGGCUUGCACAGUGCUUGGUACUGAGUAGGCACUCCGUCAGUAUUUUAGUAGCUAUUAUUCCAAAGGACACUGUAUUCUAGGUACUAAGACAAUGUGAAUGGAAUGGAAAACAAUUCCUCCCUGCAGAAGCCAACUGUCUAGGAAGACAGAUAAUGACAUUAUUAAAAUAAUCAGAACAUUGGCAAAAUAAAGAAGAUUGAAAUGCAGUUCAUAUGACAGUGCUAAUUAAUCAUACUUUUUAGAUCUAGGAAAGGCCAUAAAGGUUAAAUUGACUUGGAAAUGGUAAACAAGACAAUGGUUGUGUCACUGAUCGGUGAUGGCCAGUUUUUGGUUAUCCUUAUUUGCCAUUUAAAUGAUUGAAUUGAAAGGAAGAAGUAAGACUUGGAAGAUGAAUAUUGAAGGAAAGGUGAAGAUGGAAAAGAGAAGGGGGUUUAUUCUGAGAACAGUGACUAGAACUCUGAGGUAUGGUAGAAAUUUCAGGAUAACAGAUGAUAAAGGGGAAUGAAGCCAUGGAGAGGAAGAGAAUGAUAAUAUUAAUUGUGAAAGUUUGUGUCAAGUGUUUUCUGAGUCACCUUUCUUUCAGUUUCUCAUUUCUAGUAUUGUAUAAAUGAGUUUAACAUCAAAAUGGUAUAGUGAAAAAAAGGAUGAACUGCUUGACAGAAGAGGUCAGAUCUAGUUUUGACUCUAGCUUAUUUAGCUUUACAGCUUUAAAUAAAUUACAGUGUCUUUAAAGCUCUGGAUCUUAAGUUUUCUAAUUGUUUUUUAAACAAAGAUUUGUGAACACCUACUUACAAUGUGACAAAUGUCUUUGUAAGGCAUUAUGGGAGAUAAAAGCUGCAUUAAACCUGGCUGUUGUACUUACAAGUAAUUUGGAAGGCAAAAUUUCAAAUACUUGAACCUAAAGUAGGGUUUCUUGGUUUUCAUUUAAUUGAAAUACUGUUAGGAAACAAAAAUUUUUCAUAAAUUUUUCUUGUGGAUAUGUAAGUAAAUUCUAUAUAUCUAGCAAUAUGAUACAUCUAUAGUUCUGUUUAAAGGUAACAAUGUGAGGAAGCUUAUGCGAAUAACUUGACAGAAGAAAUCUAAAGUAAAAGCAUUUUCCUAGUAGGCUAGCUUGUUCUCUUAUUUCAUUUAUUGUAACAGUUUCACUUUUUAAUAAUUAUGUGAAAUUAGGAAACAGAUAUUCUAGGGCAUUCUGUUUAGGGUGAUGAACUUAUUCAUGAAUGUUAUUAAAACCAUUUAAAUAUGCCAUAGUUUAAAUUUGUGAUCCAUGCUGUUCAAUCUGUGACCUAGGAUAGCAGCAUCAAGGAGCAUUGUGUACAUGCAGAAGUGCACAGUACCUGGAGUGAAACUGCUUGUGUUCGAUUUCUGAUACCAUUCAUAACUGGCUGUGUGAUCUCAAAUAAGAAAACUGAAGAACCAGCUGGGCGCGGUAGCUCACGCCUGUAAUCCCAGCACUUUGGGAGGCUGAGGCGGGUGGAUUACCUGAGAACCUCUAAAAUGCAGACCUCCAGCUCUAGAUCUGUGCACCUGAGUGAAUGGCAGAAGAAUUACUUCGCAAUUACAUCUGGCAUAUGUACCGGACCGAAGGCAGAUGCAUACCGUGCACAGAUAUUACGCAUUCAGUAUGCAUGGGCAAACUCUGAGAUUUCCCAGGUCUGUGCUACCAAACUGUUCAAAAAAUAUGCAGAGAAAUAUUCUGCAAUUAUUGAUUCUGACAAUGUUGAAUCUGGGUUGAAUAAUUAUGCAGAAAACAUUUUAACUUUGGCAGGAUCUCAACAAACAGAUAGUGACAAGUGGCAGUCUGGAUUGUCAAUAAAUAAUGUUUUCAAAAUGAGUAGUGUACAGAAGAUGAUGCAAGCUGGCAAAAAAUUCAAAGACUCUCUGUUGGAACCUGCUCUUGCAUCAGUGGUAAUCCAUAAGGAGGCCACUGUCUUUGAUCUUCCUAAAUUUAGUGUUUGUGGUAGUUCUCAAGAGAGUGACUCAUUACCUAACUCAGCUCAUGAUCGAGACCGGACCCAAGACUUCCCGGAGAGCAAUCGUUUGAAACUCCUUCAGAAUGCCCAGCCACCUAUGGUGACUAACACUGCUAGGACUUGUCCUACAUUCUCAGCACCUGUAGGUGAGUCAGCUACUGCAAAAUUCCAUGUCACACCAUUGUUUGGAAAUGUCAAAAAGGAAAAUCACAGCUCUGCAAAAGAAAACAUAGGACUUAAUGUGUUCUUAUCUAACCAGUCUUGUUUUCCUGCUGCCUGUGAAAAUCCACAGAGGAAGUCUUUUUAUGGUUCUGGCACCAUUGAUGCACUUUCCAAUCCAAUACUGAAUAAGGCUUGUAGUAAAACAGAAGAUAAUGGCCCAAAGGAGGAUAGCAGCCUGCCUACAUUUAAAACUGCAAAAGAACAAUUAUGGGUAGAUCAGCAAAAAAAGUACCACCAACCUCAGCGUGCAUCAGGGUCUUCAUAUGGUGGUGUAAAAAAGUCUCUAGGAGCUAGUAGAUCCCGAGGGAUACUUGGAAAGUUUGUUCCUCCUAUACCCAAGCAAGAUGGGGGAGAGCAGAAUGGAGGAAUGCAAUGUAAGCCUUAUGGGGCAGGACCUACAGAACCAGCACAUCCAGUUGAUGAGCGUCUGAAGAACUUGGAGCCAAAGAUGAUUGAACUUAUUAUGAAUGAGAUUAUGGAUCAUGGACCUCCAGUAAAUUGGGAAGAUAUUGCAGGAGUAGAAUUUGCUAAAGCCACCAUAAAGGAAAUAGUUGUGUGGCCCAUGUUGAGGCCAGACAUCUUUACUGGUUUAAGGGGACCCCCUAAAGGAAUUUUGCUCUUUGGUCCUCCUGGGACUGGUAAAACUCUAAUUGGCAAGUGCAUUGCUAGUCAGUCUGGGGCAACAUUCUUUAGCAUCUCUGCUUCAUCCUUAACUUCUAAAUGGGUAGGUGAGGGGGAGAAAAUGGUCCGUGCAUUGUUUGCUGUUGCAAGGUGUCAGCAACCAGCUGUGAUAUUUAUUGACGAAAUUGAUUCCUUGUUAUCUCAACGGGGAGAUGGUGAGCAUGAAUCUUCUAGAAGGAUAAAAACAGAAUUUUUAGUUCAAUUAGAUGGAGCAACAACAUCUUCUGAAGAUCGUAUCCUAGUGGUGGGAGCAACAAAUCGGCCACAAGAAAUUGAUGAGGCUGCCCGGAGAAGAUUGGUGAAAAGGCUUUAUAUUCCCCUCCCAGAAGCUUCAGCCAGGAAACAGAUAGUAAUUAAUCUAAUGUCCAAAGAGCAGUGUUGCCUCAGUGAAGAAGAAAUUGAACAGAUUGUACAGCAGUCUGAUGCGUUUUCAGGAGCAGACAUGACACAGCUUUGCAGGGAGGCUUCUCUUGGUCCUAUUCGCAGUUUACAAACUGCUGACAUUGCUACCAUAACACCGGAUCAAGUUCGACCCAUAGCUUACAUUGAUUUUGAAAAUGCUUUUAGAACUGUGCGACCUAGUGUUUCUCCAAAAGAUUUAGAGCUUUAUGAAAACUGGAACAAAACUUUUGGUUGUGGAAAGUAAGUGGGAUACUUGGAAUCAAGGCAUCUCUGUAGUACAGUCUUCUUUAUUUUUUAGCAUAGAAAGUUGGGGAUGUGUUAAUUGUAUUUUUAAGAAUAUAUUCUAAGUUCUGUACUUCAAAUAAUAGCACAGAUUUUACAUCUGAUUGACAUAGUGUAUGUUAAUGUAAGUUUUGCUUUCCAGUGAUUACCUGAUACGUAAGCCUAUUUGAACAAAGUGAGAAUGAACUUUUGUUUCUAAGAAGUCUUUAUCUUGAAGCUAUAUAACAUGAAAAGUGAGCUCAAAUUUUUUUUAGUUGAAGAUUACAUAUAAAGUUGUGUCUGAUUAAUAUUCAUCUUUUAUUGAAGAAAGUGCCUUCUGAUGGCCACAUAAUUCUUAAUGUCAGCUAGUAUAAUGGUUUACAUUUGGACAAAGUAUUGCUUAGUGUUAUUUAAGUAGAUUUAAGAUCUCAAAGCUAAAGUGCCAAUUUUUACUUUCUUCAGCCAAUUUGUUACCUCUUUUAUGGUUUUUAAUUUUUAUCAGGACUAACAUUUUCAGAAAUAGCAAGGUGUGAUCUAGUAUUAGAUUCACAGAACUGAAAGGUUAAUUAAGAAUGUUGGUUAUUUUCACGGGAGCGUGUGAUAUUUAACAUUAAUAUUUUAUUUGACACUACAGCCUGUAAUACUGCUCUCUUUCAAAAACAAGUUUUCAGAUUUUUAUAACAGACCCAUUUUGUUUUAUGAAACAUGUUCAUUACAGAAACAUGAGAAAAUAGAGAUAAGUAAAAAGAAUAAAAGUCACUAUUAUCCUACCACUUUGCGGGACACACUAUUAAUAUUUAAGCAUAGAUUCUUCCAGAUGUUUUGUUUUAUACAGCAGUAGGAUUGUGUAAUGUAUUCUCUCUUGUAGCCUAUUCUUCAAAGCGUAUCUUCACUUUCCAUGUUAACAUAAAUGUCCUUUUAUGAUUGUCUAGGAUUCCAUGGAUGGAUGGAAUAUAAUUGAGUCAUCUGGUAGAGCGCAUAUAGGACAGGACGCUAGGUUGUUUAUCUUUUGUUUAUUGUAAAGGAACUAUGUGGGAUGCAUUUGGUGAUCUUUUUAAAAAAUGUAUAAAUUUCUUGAGUAAUUCCUGGAUUAAAGAAUAUGCACUUUUUAAA